AACAUGGAGAUUUUGUACCAUGUCCUGUUCUUAGUGCUUGAAUGUCCUAACCUGAAGCUGAAGAAGCCGCCCUGGCUGCACAUGCUGUCGGCCAUGACUGUAUGCUCUGGUGGUGGUGUCUUCCUCAUUACCGGAGGAAUCAUUUAUGAUGUUAUUGUUGAACCUCCAAGUGUUGGCUCUAUGACUGAUGAACAUGGGCAUCAGAGGCCAGUAGCUUUCUUUGCCUAUAGAGUAAAUGGACAAUAUAUUAUGGAAGGACUUGCAUCCAGCUUCCUGUUUACAAUGGGAGGUUUAGGUUUCAUAAUCCUGGACCAAUUGAAUGCACCAAAUAUCCCAAAACUCAAUAGAUUUCUUCUUCUAUUCAUUGGAUUUGUCUGUGUUCUAUUGAGUAUUUUCAUGGCUAGAGUAUUCAUGAGAAUGAAACUGCCGAGCUAUCUGAUGGGUUAGAGUGCCUUUGAGAAGAAAUCAGUGGAUACUGGAUUUUUUCUUGUCAAUGAAGUUUUAAAGGCUGUACCAAUCCUCUAAUAUGAAAUGUGGAAAAGAAUGAAGAGCAGCAGUAAAAGAAACUUCUAGUGAAAAAACAGGAA